ACAAAUCAGCGACCGAACUCUGGCGGUGGUGGUUAAGACGGCGAAGGCGGCAGCGGCGGCGACAGCUCUGGGGUUUGCGUCUCGGGGUGUGUCGGCCGCCGCUGCUGCUUGGGCCUGGUAUGUACAGAUGGCUGGUUAGGAUUCUCGGCACCAUUUUCCGUUUCUGCGACCGGUCGGUGCCCCCUGCCCGGGCCCUCCUGAAGAGGCGGCGCUCAGACAGCACUCUGUUUUCUACAGUGGACACUGAUGAAAUACCAGCCAAAAGACCAAGAUUAGAUUGCUUUAUUCACCAAGUGAAAAACAGUCUCUACAAUGCUGCCAGCUUAUUUGGAUUCCCAUUCCAGCUGACCACAAAGCCCAUGGUAACUUCUGCUUGUAAUGGAACACGGAAUGUGGCCCCUUCAGGAGAGGUAUUUUCGAACUCUUCAUCUUGUGAACUGACAGGUUCUGGAUCCUGGAACAACAUGCUGAAACUGGGUAAUAAAUCUCCUAAUGGAAUAAGUGACUAUCCAAAGAUCAGAGUGACAGUUACCCGAGAUCAGCCACGCAGAGUCCUGCCUUCCUUUGGUUUUACUUUGAACUCAGAAGGCUGUAAUAGAAGACCAGGUGGCCGUCGCCAUAGCAAAGGUAAUCCAGAGAGUUCUUUAAUGUGGAAACCUCAGGAACAGGCUGUAACAGAGAUGAUUUCUGAAGAGAGUGGCAAGGGUCUGAGGCGUCCCCAUUGUACUGUGGAGGAGGGUGUUCAAAAAGAGGAAAGAGAGAAGUACCGAAAGUUAUUGGAACGACUUAAAGAAAGUGGUCAUGGAAACUCUGUCUGUCCUGUAACUUCAAAUUAUCACAGUUCUCAAAGAAGUCAGAUGGACACAUUAAAGACCAAAGGCUGGGGGGAAGAGCAAAAUCACGGAGUCAAAACAACUCAGUUUGUUCCAAAACAAUAUAGACUUGUUGAAACAAGGGGACCUCUAUGUUCAUUGAGAAGUGAAAAGAGGUGUUCAAAGGGGAAAAUUACUGAUACAGAGACGAUGGUCGGAAUCAGAUUUGAAAAUGAAAGUAGGAGGGGAUACCAACUGGAGCCUGACCUAUCAGAAGAAGUGUCGGCCCGACUCCGCCUGGGCAGUGGAAGCAAUGGCUUACUCAGGAGGAAAGUGUCAAUAAUUGAGACAAAGGAAAAGAAUUGCUCAGGCAAAGAGAGGGACAGAAGAACGGACGAUCUCCUUGAACUUACAGAGGACAUGGAAAAGGAAAUCAGUAAUGCCCUAGGCCAUGGCCCACAGGAUGAAAUCCUAAGUAGUGCUUUCAAAUUGCGAAUUACUCGAGGAGAUAUUCAGACAUUAAAGAACUAUCACUGGCUCAAUGAUGAAGUCAUUAAUUUUUACAUGAAUCUUCUGGUGGAAAGAAAUAAAAAGCAAGGCUAUCCAGCACUUCAUGUAUUCAGUACUUUCUUCUAUCCUAAAUUAAAGUCUGGGGGUUACCAAGCAGUGAAACGAUGGACCAAAGGGGUAAAUCUCUUUGAACAAGAAAUUAUUCUGGUGCCUAUUCAUCGGAAGGUACAUUGGAGCCUGGUGGUGAUUGACCUAAGAAAAAAGUGUCUUAAAUAUCUGGAUUCUAUGGGACAAAAGGGCCACAGGAUCUGUGAGAUUCUCCUUCAGUAUUUACAGGAUGAAAGUAAGACCAAAAGAAAUAGUGAUCUGAAUCUUUUAGAGUGGACCCAUCACAGCAUGAAACCACACGAGAUUCCUCAACAGCUGAAUGGGAGUGAUUGUGGAAUGUUUACUUGUAAAUAUGCAGAUUAUAUUUCUAGGGACAAACCUAUCACAUUUACUCAGCACCAGAUGCCUCUCUUCCGGAAGAAGAUGGUGUGGGAAAUCCUUCAUCAGCAGUUGCUGUGAGAAAACUUUGCCUGGUCCCUCUAGCUGCUGGUGGUUCUUUCACAGACAUUUCCAUAUACCUCAUGCAUUGUGGGUUAAAAAGUCCCUGCAUCACUUCUGUUCUCACAGGUACUGAGCUGUCAAAAGUGCAUGAAGGCCUCUCACUGUACUCUAGUCCUGACUUGGGGUGCAGAGGGCUGCUUGCAAUCCUGUUUGUAAGGCUGUGCCUGCUCAGAGCUUUGGACUGUUCAACCCACACAAGAACAAACGCUAACUAAUAUUUUUUUUAAGAGAUUCUUUUCCCUAUGAAUGUGGGAAAUGCAGGAUUUAUUCUGUGAAUUGUUUGUUUCUGUGUGUUUGUUCAGCGUAUUCAUUCACUCACUCGUUUGCAAACAUAAUGGGCAGUGGUCAUUUACUGCUGCUCUUUUACAGUUAGCUCUAAAUUACUUGUUUGAACUAUUUAUUUCUGAAAGGAAUGUUACUCAAGCUGCCACUCCCUGCUGAAGAGCAGGAGGGAACUCUCACUGGGGGCGGAAGGAAGUGGAGCUGGAGCAGUAACUGCCAACAUGAAGCUGGAGGGUUUGGGAUUUUUUUUGUUUUUGUUUUUUUGAGGCUCAAAAAAUGCUGGGAGAAAUGAAAAUGCUGUGGGAUAGGGCUCCUGUUGCCUUUCAGAGGAAGUCUGACACUACAGCGUUGGCACAGUGCCGUGAACAGUGGAACUGUGCCCAAGGGACUCUGAUUAUCCAAGCAUCUUCCGAAGAGUGUUGUGGUCACCUUAAAGAGACUUCCCCUUCUGGAAAUGUGGUGACUUGGCUUAGUCUUCAAACUGGAUUCAUGGAUUUGAAGUAACUGUAAACCCUAAAUCUUCAUUUUCAUCCCAGAUCUGGUUGAGUAUAAACCUCAGAAUUGUAGGGGCUGGCCUGAGCUGUUUAUUUCAAAAGAUACUAUUCAAUUUAAAGCUAUUUUUCCUCAGAGUUUUUGUUUUCUAUAUAUUAAGUCUAAAUUAAGUUUUCUACUCAUUAAGACUAACAUCUCCCCACUCCAUCCCCACUGAAAUUUGUGGAAGAAAAUUUAGUACUUGGCUCUGAGGUUGCCAGUUAUACAAUAAUCUAUUUUGCAUAUGAAAGUUUGUAUUUAACUUUUUUGUUCAUUAAAAACCUUACUGAUAUGGUUAUAACUUCAGACAGUUUAGAGUUGGUCAGAACAUAUUUUGCAAGAUCUAGUGCCUAGUGUUGCUUUUCUGAUGUAAUAAAAGGUGGUCUGGCAGAACCUAAAAAAGUAUAUGCUGAAAUGAUUUCUAACCCUCUCCCUACUUAAACCUCCCAGACUUGUUCUGGUUCAUAAAAGCAAGAGGUAAAACUGGAAAAAUUGUGCACGUGUUACCUAUGAAUCUACACGCCUGCCAUUUGCAGUGCUCCGGCUGCUGGUCCCAGAGGUAUACUGGUUACAGCUAUUGCAGCCAGUUCCCUGAGACUUGUAAAACUCCUGGUUUAGGACAUGGGGCCUGUGGUGUGGAUGGAAAAUGCUGGGCCUACUGGAUGGUCAGCCAGAGGCCAUGUGGUGGGUGAUGACUGAAGCGGGAGCAGGUUGUACCACACCUCUCCCCCCCCCCUCCCACUCCCCCUCCCUCCCUCUCCCCUCCCCCUCCCUCCCUCCCCCCUCCCUCCCUCCCCCCCCUCCCCCUCCCUCCCCCUCCCUCUCUCCCUAACACCCACCCUCCCCCUUUCCCCCACCCUCCCCCCUUCUCCCCUUUCCCCACCCUCCCUCCCCCCUUCCCCCUCCCCCCCCCCCCCCCGCAGCCCCUGCUCCUUUCUCUGGGCUCCUGGCAUUGUGCCAGUGAGUGCUGGGACCAGGUAAUGAGCACAGCCAAAAAGGCCAGAGGUUCACUAGGUCAGCAUCAUACCAAACGCCUGGCUUUCACCAGGCAUCAGUGUGCUUCACUUGAGAGUUUGGUACCAUGGUUAAGAUCGAGUCCAUGCUAGGUAAGUCCUGUUAGGAAUGUCAGUUUGUAUUCCGCCCACGUGAAUGAUGCUGAGCUUAAUGUAUUAUUUUGAGGGGCUUCUUCAGAGCAGUUCUCACUGAGCUUUCCAUUAACCUACACUCUUCCGGACGGCUCUUAAAACUUGCAGGACAUAAUGAAAUUGGGAAGAGCAGAGUGUUGAAGUCUAUAGCAUGGCCUUCUGCUUGACCCUGAGUUCCUGAAUUGAAUGUGGGAGACCACAGGCCAUACUUCUCUAGGCACUCACAUGUCUCCCUUGGCAUAAGGAAACAUGUUAGUAAUAUAGUUUUUUAGAUCCAAACAGUUUAUUUGGAUCUAAAAGUUUAAGUGUUCAGUUGAAAAACAGCUAUUGAUUUUAUUAGUAGCAAAUUAUCACCAUUAAAGCCAGUGGUUUUUUUUUUGUUUUUUUUUUUUGUUUUUUUUUUUUUUUUUUGCGACAGAGUCUCUUGUCGCCCAGGCUGGAGUACAAUGGUGUGAUCUCAGCUCACUGCAACCUCCGCCUCCCAGGUUCAAGCGAUUCUCCUGCCUCAGCCUCCUGCGUAGCUGGGAUUACAGGUGCCCACCACCACACCCUGCUAAUUUUUGUACUUUUAGUAGAGAUGGGGUUUCGCCAUGUUGGCCAGGCUGGUCUUGAACUGCUGACCUCAGGUGAUCCACCCGCCUCGGCCUCCCAAAGUGCUGGUAUUACAGUCAUGAGCCACCUCACCCAGCCUGUUUUUGAGACGGAGUUUCACUUUUGUCGCCCAGGCUGGAGUGCAAUGGCGCUAUCUCAGCUCACUGCAACCCCCACCUCCCAGGUUCAAGCGAUUCUCCUGCCUCAGCCUCCCGAGUAGCUGGGAUUACAGGCAUGUGCCACCACCCCUGGCUAAUUUUGUAUUUUUAGUGGAGACGGGGUUUCUCCAUGUUGGUCAGGCUGGUCUUAAACUCCCGACCUCAAGUGAUCUGCCCGCCUCGGCCUCCCAAAGUGCUGGGAUUACAGGCGUGAGCCAUUGCACCUGUCCCUGCCAGUGUGUUUUUAAAAUAGUUUAGGGGGUUGAGAAAAGAUGCAGUGAGCCAUUAUUCUCCUUUAGCAGGUAGUCUCUUAAAAAUUGAUGUGGAUUUUAAAAAUAUACCAUUGAGAACACGUAUCUUUCUCAAACUUGACCUUGAACAGAGCUGGAUGGGGGUGGGAGGGAAACAGAUUUGGGGCAUAUGGAAGAUAUUCUUGGGAGCCCCAUAUUCUACCUCAGUUACCGAAGGCUAUUAGAACCUCUGAAUUUUUCCUCCUCUGAAAUCCUAAGCACAACUUCAGAAAACCAUGUCUGAUAGCGGAUGUCUUCCUGCUGUGAGGAGCUGCUUGAUGUGGGGACCAAGGUGUGGGUGUGGGCGGAAUGUAUCCUAGUAGAAACAGUGAACCUCAGAUAUGAAUAAAUAAGCAAGAGACCGAAAGUUAAGUGUGUGACAACCUCAGUACUGUAGUUAAGCUACAUUCUUUAAAUUAGCUUUUGUGAACUGAUUGGGAACCUAAUCUCUUUUGUAACUGUUUGAGAAAAACUCUGAAGCACCUGAUAUUCAAACAAACUUAUGGUACUUACUAACUCAUUUGUAAAUUGGCGAUGUAGCUGGCUGUAGUAUUGCUUUGAUAAUUUUUUUCUUUUAAUUUACCUAAUAUAUAUAAGGAAGGGGUUUGGAUAUAUUAAAAUAGGUGUUAAUUUUAUCUAUUUACCAAUAAAUUCAUCUCUUUAAUUCA